CUAAAUAGCCGCAGCCUCUGCGCGUCGCCCUCCACGGUUACCCCGGCUCUCCGCCCCUCCUUCUCGCGGCGCUCGAGGGACCAUGGCCGAUCCUCGCGUGAGACAGAUCAAGAUCAAGACCGGCGUGGUGAAGCGGUUGGUCAAAGAAAAAGUGAUGUAUGAAAAAGAGGCAAAACAACAAGAAGAAAAGAUUGAAAAAAUGAGAGCUGAAGACGGUGAAAAUUAUGACAUUAAAAAGCAGGCAGAGAUCCUACAAGAAUCCAGGAUGAUGAUCCCAGAUUGCCAGCGCAGGUUGGAAGCCGCAUAUUUGGAUCUUCAACGGAUACUAGUAAGCAAAGACUUCUGUGUCAUGUUUAAAUUUUUUUUUUCAAUCCAAUACAUGGAAAGCCAAAAGUUUAAAUAUUUAACACUGAGAACUAGUUGGCAGUAUUUCUUAUUCACUUGCCCUUUAUACCGCUAUAUUUUAAAAUAAUUAAUGGAGUUUAAAUUGUGUUUUGAAUUAUGCCUCCAGUAAAAGUACUGUUUUCUAGCAUGUUUGUUCAGUUUAUUAAAAUUUAGCUAGUUAAAUUUAUUUAAGUUAUGAUAGUACCAGUAUUGUCCAGCAAUGUCUUGAUUAUUUGGUUUUCAUACAUAAAGAUCUUUUGAGACAUUGAGGAUGAGUUGACUGAUUAAAAUUUUAAAAGAUCUAAUGUUUCAAAAGAAUUUGGGAUCUUAUUAAAAGGAUCUUGAAUUCUUUCACAUUCAAACCUAGAUCAGUUUGAGAGGGGGAAAAAACCUGGUAAUCUAUGUAGUCCCCUCAUACUAACUUGGAGCUGAAUAACACUUAUACUUGCUGGUAUAAAUGCCUUGUGAUACAGAAGGUAGAUAAAGCAGGAAAUAAUAACUGUUAAAAUACUAUCUAAGACAGGAAGCAUCAUUUGUAUUUCUUGACAGUUUAAAUGCUUUUUUCUCUCAUGAAUCUAGUAGCUGAGAAAGUAAUAGAAAUUGCUUGGAAAAAAAUAAUGUUGGCCGCCAGGUGCAGUGGCUCAUGCCUGUAAUCCCAGCACUUUGGGAGGCUGAGGUGGGUGGAUCACGAGUCAGGAGUUCAAGACCAGCCUGACCAACAUGGUGAAAUCCUGUCUCUACUAAAAAUACCAAAAUAAUAAUAAUAAUAAUAAUGUAUUUGGAUGAUAUAUUUGUAUGUGAAGAUGUAUUCAACAAUAUCUCUGCCCUUGAAGAGCUUGUAUUUACUAACAGAGAACAAAGAUGUGUUUAAGGUAUAACAUGGAGGUUUAAGAAAUUCUUACGUAUAGUUUGAGCUAAGCAAAUUCUCAGUCGUUUUGCUUUCAGUUUUCAUAUUAAAUACACACAUACUUUAUUUCCUCUACUGUUUGUAUAUCUCCAUCUUUUAUUGACCUGACAUAAAUUGCUAACCAUAGCUUCAUUUAAAAAUCAAACAAAAUUUCCUGUGUACUUUAGAUAAUAUUAUUUCAUUUGUCUGUUAUCAUUACAAUAUAUUAGUAAAAGUUGCCUGUAUAUCAGUAUUAUGGAAAAACUCAAUCUUUAAAUAUCAGAAAAUGAAAGAUGUAUUUUGUUUCCUUUAGUGUAGGGUAUGUAAUACCCAUUAGCAAGCAGGCAAUUCAUUUGUUUAAUUCAAAGAUUAUAUUUAACUCUGUUGUGACAUCAGAAGCCUUCUUUGUCAUUGUGAAUAGUCAGUGGAUUAUUUUGGCCUGAAUGCUGUCAUAUAUGUAACAUGUUAGUAAAUCUUCCUUUUUACUUUUCUCUUUUGUAUGAUGAUGAUGGGUCAACAAAAUGAGAAUAAACUUUUUCUGAGGUUUUUAUUUAAUUAAUGCUGGUAGCUUUAGAAGACUGUUAUUCACUUAUUUUAUGAGAAUAUAUACAGUGAAACAAAACCACCAGUUAUUUCUUCCUUUCCUUGUAAAGAAGGAACAGAAUGUGGGAAACCUGUGGAAUUACAAUAUAUUUAGAUGAGGCUUGGGAUUUUUUACUUUUAAUUUUUUAGUUAUUAACAUUAAUGGUUUGUAAUAUUUGAGUAAAUAACAAAGUACUGAAACUUGAAAAGGAUAAACUUAAUUUUUAUUGUAUUUCAUUUUAGGAAAAUGAAAAAGACUUGGAAGAAGCUGAGGAAUAUAAAGAAGCACGUUUAGUACUGGAUUCAGUGAAGUUAGAAGCCUGAAACUUUUCUCGUAUGGGGUGGUUUUUGCAUUAAAUCCUGGGGUCCAUUUUACAAUCCAUUAUUUUUGACCACUGCUAUGUGUUCAAGUAGUAUGAGAAUGUGAUUGUUUUUAUCUGGUUACAUAUAUAUUUCUUUGUCUAAUUUAAUAUGUCAAAUAAAUGAGUUCAUCUAAUAAAAUUGUUUAUUUUAUACUUUACAAAAUUUUUAAAUUAACCUUUUAUCAUUAAACCACAUAGACUUUAUGACAGAGAA